GUGGCAGAGCGAAGCUGAGGAGUCCAGCGCUCGCCGACAGGGGCCUGGGCUGUCCCGAGCCGGGUCUCGCUCUGUUACUCAGGCUGGAGUGCAGUGGCACACUGCAGCCUCAACCUCCCGGGCUCAAGCGAUCCUCCAAUCUCAGCCUCCCAAGUAGCUGGGACUACAGGAAUCCAGAUCUUACAUAAGAUGGAAGUCUCUCACACUAGAUACUGAACAUUAAAUAGAAAAUCUAUUUAGUAAAAUCUAAGUUGCCAUGGAAGAAAUACCAGUAAAAGUUGCUGUAAGAAUUAGACCUCUGCUUUGCAAAGAAGCUCUUCAUAAUCAUCAAGUUUGUGUGAGAGUUAUUCCAAACAGCCAGCAAGUUAUCAUUGGGAGAGAUAGAGUCUUCACUUUUGAUUUUGUUUUUGGCAAAAAUUCCACUCAAGAUGAAGUUUAUAACACAUGUAUAAAGCCCCUAGUGUUGUCACUCAUUGAGGGCUAUAAUGCAACUGUUUUUGCCUAUGGACAAACUGGAUCUGGGAAGACAUACACCAUUGGAGGGGGCCAUAUUGCUUCAGUUGUGGAGGGCCAAAAGGGUAUCAUUCCUCGAGCUAUUCAAGAAAUAUUUCAAAGCAUCUCUGAACAUCCUAGCAUUGACUUUAAUGUAAAAGUAUCUUAUAUAGAAGUGUACAAGGAAGACCUAAGAGAUCUUCUAGAAUUGGAGACAUCCAUGAAGGAUCUUCACAUCCGAGAAGAUGAAAAAGGAAACACAGUGAUUGUUGGGGCCAAGGAAUGCCAUGUGGAGAGUGCAGGUGAAGUGAUGAGUCUUUUGGAGAUGGGGAAUGCAGCCAGACAUACAGGUACCACUCAAAUGAAUGAGCACUCCAGCAGAUCACAUGCAAUUUUUACAAUCAGCAUUUGUCAAGUUCAUAAAAAUAUGGAGGCAGCUGAAGAUGGAUCAUGGUAUUCCCCUCGGCAUAUUGUCUCAAAGUUCCACUUUGUGGAUUUGGCAGGAUCAGAAAGAGUAACCAAAACGGGGAAUACUGGUGAACGGUUCAAAGAAUCCAUUCAAAUCAAUAGUGGAUUGCUGGCUUUAGGAAAUGUAAUAAGCGCUCUUGGGGACCCACGCAGGAAGAGUUCACAUAUUCCAUAUAGGGAUGCUAAAAUUACCCGGCUUCUGAAAGAUUCUCUGGGAGGCAGUGCUAAGACUGUCAUGAUCACAUGUGUCAGCCCCUCCUCCUCGAAUUUUGAUGAGUCCUUAAAUUCUCUCAAAUAUGCCAACAGAGCACGGAACAUUAGAAACAAACCCACUGUAAACUUCAGCCCCGAGUCAGACCGUAUAGAUGAAAUGGAAUUUGAGAUUAAAUUGCUUCGAGAAGCUUUGCAAAGCCAGCAGGCUGGUGUCAGCCAAACUACCCAGAUCAAUCGAGAAGGGAGUCCUGAUACAAAUAGGAUUCAUUCUCUUGAGGAGCAAGUAGCUCAGCUUCAAGGAGAAUGUCUGGGUUACCAGUGUUGUGUAGAAGAAGCCUUUACCUUCCUGGUUGACCUAAAAGAUACUGUCAGACUAAACGAAAAGCAGCAACACAAACUGCAGGAGUGGUUUAACAUGAUCCAAGAGGUCAGGAAGGCUGUCCUCACCUCAUUUCGAGGAAUCGGAGGCACUGCAAGUCUGGAAGAAGGACCACAGCAUGUUACAGUUCUCCAGCUGAAGAGAGAGCUUAAGAAAUGCCAGUGUGUGCUUGCUGCUGAUGAAGUAGUAUUUAAUCAGAAGGAACUGGAGGUGAAGGAACUGAAGAAUCAAGUGCAGAUGAUGGUACAGGAAAACAAAGGGCAUGCUGUAUCUUUGAAAGAAGCGCAAAAAGUGAAUAGACUGCAGAAUGAAAAAAUAAUAGAACAACAACUUCUUGUGGAUCAACUGAGUGAAGAACUAACAAAACUUAACCUGUCAGUGACUUCUUCAGCUAAAGAAAAUUGUGGAGAUGGGCCAGAUGCCAGGAUCCCUGAAAGGAGACCAUAUACUGUACCAUUUGAUACUCAUUUGGGGCAUUAUAUUUAUAUCCCAUCAAGACAAGAUUCCAGGAAGGUCCACACAAGUCCGCCUAUGUACUCUCUGGAUCGAAUAUUUGCUGGAUUUCGAACACGAAGUCAGAUGCUGUUGGGUCACAUAGAAGAACAAGAUAAGGUCCUCCACUGCCAAUUUUCUGAUAACAGUGAUGAUGAAGAAUCAGAAGGCCAAGAGAAAUCUGGAACUAGAUGUAGAAGUCGUUCAUGGAUUCAGAAGCCAGACUCUGUUUGUUCCCUUGUUGAAUUGAGUGAUACUCAGGAUGAAACACAAAAGUCAGAUUUGGAGAAUGAAGAUUUAAAGAUUGAUUGUCUCCAGGAGAGUCAAGAAUUGAAUUUGCAAAAAUUAAAGAAUUCAGAACGCAUACUUACUGAAGCUAAACAAAAAAUGAGAGAACUUACAAUUAACAUCAAGAUGAAGGAAGAUCUGAUUAAAGAAUUAAUAAAAACAGGUAAUGAUGCCAAGUCUGUAAGCAAGCAGUAUUCUUUGAAAGUAACAAAGCUAGAGCAUGAUGCAGAACAGGCAAAAGUCGAACUGAUUGAAACACAAAAGCAGCUACAGGAGCUGGAAAACAAAGAUCUUUCUGAUGUUGCAAUGAAGGUAAAAUUACAGAAAGAGUUUCGUAAAAAGAUGGAUGCUGCAAAGCUGAGAGUUCAGGAAAUACAAUUAAAAACAGGACAGGAAGAAGGUCUAAAACCGAAAGCUGAGGACCUUGAUGCAUGUAACUUGAAAAGGAGAAAAGGUUCGUUUGGAAGUAUAGACCAUCUCCAGGCCUUAAACACAGAUAGUUUGAAAAUAUCAACUCGCCUGAACUUACUGGAACAAGAGUUGUCUGAAAAGAAUGUGCAGCUCCAGACCAGUACAGCUGAGGAGAAAACAAAGAUUUCAGAACAAGUUGAAGUCCUCCAGAAAGAAAAGGAUCAGCUCCAGAAACGCAGACACAAUGUGGAUGAAAAACUUAAAAAUGGUAGAGUGUUAUCACCUGAAGUAAGUCAGUAUUCUUUGGAACUGGAGGUGCUGUAUGAUGGAUCACUUGAGUGAUUUCCUCAGUCUUUUUCACAUAAUCAUAAAUAUUAUCUGGUAAACUUGGUUCCUUGAGAUUUUGUCAGAUGUAGUGAGUUCACCUGGCACUUAUUUGGCACCAUAAACCACGCUGGACUAGAGACUGAGAUAUCCUUACAUAGUGGUCCAUGGACAUGGCCCCUUCCUGGCACUGCCAGGCAUUUGGAAACUAUUACUUUCCUUGAGUAUAUUUGCCUCCUCAGCUGGGGUUUCUCGUCUGAAAUCACAGAACAUAGAAAAUGAUUUGAGGGACUCUUCUGGAGGGCACCUGACUUUUCUCUAUACAUAUUUCUUGAAUGAUACUAGGUAAUUUAUUACAUACAAGAGAUGCCUAAGGAAUUAGGGGUUAAUUCUUUCCAUGAAACCUUGGUUUAGAAGGCCCAGUGUCCAUACUAUGUCCAGCCAAAUAGAUGCACAAAAUUCCAAUCCCAGUAAAAGACCUUUUAGUUAUACAGUUUUUUUAAAACUAUAGUUUUAGUUAUAGUUUUUUAAAACUAUGUAGAAGAUGAUUCAUUUAUGGGCUGUCAAAUUGCCCCAGACUUUGUCUUUUUUCAAAAUUUUCAGUCAGUUGGCAGUGGUACCUUUACCUUACUUCAUCAGAGAAAGAUGAAUUUUUGAAUCUGAACUUCCUCUGCAAAUAUUUAUUGUUGGUGUCUCAUCAUUACCAAACCAAGGGAAAAUUGCUAAGAGAAGGUGAAUAGCUGAGAAUCACACACAGUGGUGAAUCUUGUAAUGUUUUAGUUUGGAGCAAGUGACAGGAAGUUAUAGGGGCUAGUUAAGAAAUAGGAGCAAGGAUAACAUUAGAUUGUUGCUCACUGAGAAUUGAUGAAAGGAUUGACUUACAAAUCAAUCCUUGAUUGGGGGCUAAGUGGCAGUUGAAAGGAACAUUAUAGACCUCUGUUGCCCUGUUUUAUAACUUAAGCUGGGUAGCUGUGCAGAGGAACAGAGAGCCAGGCUGUCCUCCCAAGGUAUUAAAUUGGAGCCUAAGGGUUAUAGAUUUGAAGACAUGAGAGCCUAAGAUACAGCAGAAUUCAAAUAUUUAAGGAAUUCUGCCUGCCGGUGACUAUUACUAAGCUCUAUAGAAGAUAGAAGAAGCAAAAAAAAAAAAAAAAAACCCAAAGUAUUAUGUUUCCCUUGAGAAAUUAAUACUCUAUUUGGGAAAACAGAUAGAAAUAUAAGAAAACUCUAAACUCUGAAGGACAUUGAAAAUCAAGUUGUGGAUAAUGUAUUACAGCUAUACCUCUUACAUUAUUUAUUCAAAGCAAUGAAGUGAUCAUUUGGGGGAAGAUUCAUCAAGGCAGCCUCAGUAGAUCAGAAUCUUGAGCUAGAUUAUGAAAAACAUGAUAUGCACUGGCAGAUACAAGAAAGAAGUCCGUUUUAGACAGAACAUCUUUGAAGAAGGCACAGAGAUGAGAAUUAACAAAUUAUGUUUGCAGUAGGGUAGAGUUCCAUUAAUAUCAAGAAACAUUUAGGUUUCUAUUUCAUGUGGGAUCCCAUAACAAAAAACGUUAUUUACAGAUUUGUGGUGAAAAUAUAGUAUGGCGCAUGAUACCUAUUUUGCGGCUAUUCUGGACUGGGGUUUGAGGGAAUGAUGAGCCUCCUACAACUGGUAGAGUUCUACUUACUCACAUGAGCUUCUAUGCACCUUUCUUCCACAUGGUUGGUUCUUCUUAGUGUACCUCUCAAGUGAGGCUCUGCUCUUAUCACGAUUUUAAAGCCAAGGUUAAUAUUCCAAAUAGAUCUGUCACUAGCAGAUGAUCGAGAACAUGAGAUUCUGAUGUGACGACACAAGGUAUCAAUAAAAUCUAGUUGGAAUGGUUUGCUAUCUUAAUGUCUUUAAGCUUGUUUAGGAUAAUUUUCUCUUUCCACAGUAAAUUAAAAUAUUUUUCCUAAUUUUAUUACUUUAUGGAAAUGGAUAGAAAGAUUUUAGAUCGUUACACUAAUAGAAGAUUACCCAACAAUUUACUACAGACAAGUCACACCGCUUUUUUUUUUUUUUUUUGGUAAAAUCCAGAAACUAAAAUUAAAGAAUACCUGAACUUUAGAUUUCUAAUAAUACAGAGUAGUUGCUUAAUAAGUAGGGAGGAAAAUAUAAGAACUAUUAUGUUUAUCUAAUCUUUUAAACUUUUAAUUUCUCAUUUUAUGAUGAGAACAUACUUUUUUUUUUUUUUUUUGAGAUGGAGUCUCACUCUGUCACUCAGGGUGGAGUGCAGUGGUGCGAUCUCGGCUCACUGCCUCCAUCUCCUGGGUUCAAGCAAUUCUCCUGCCUCAGCCUCCCCAGUAGCUGGGAUUACAGAUGUGCGCUACCAUGCCCAGCUAAUUUUUUUUUUUUUUUUUUUUUGAGACGGAGUCUUGCUCUGUCACCAGGCUGGAGUGCAGUGGCGUGAUCUCAGCUCACUACAACCUCCGCCUGCCUGGUUCAAGCGAUUCCCCUGCCUCAGCCACCUGAGUAGCUGGCACUGCAGGCAAGUGCCAUCAUGCUUGGCUAGUUUUUUGUAUUUUAGUAGAGAUGGGGUUUCACCAUGUUGGCCAAGAUGGUCUCGAUCUCCUGACCUCAUGAUCCACCCACCUCGGCUUCCCAAAGUGCUGGGAUUACAGGUGUGAGCCACUGCACCUGGCCUAAUUUUUGUAUUUUUAGUAGAGAUGAGGUUUCGCCAUGUUGGUCAGGCUGGUCUCGAACUCCUGACCUCAAGUGAUCCACCCGCCUCAGCCUCCCAAAGUGCUGGGUUUACAGGCCUUGAACCACCACACCCUGCCGAGAACAUAAAAUUUACAGGGAAAUCUCUGCAGUGCUUGCUCAAAAGUUGUUGUUAGUUUUUUGUUUCAUUUUACUUGGUCUCUGGACCAGCAGCAACAGCAUCACUUGGAGGCUUGUUAGAAAUGCAGAUCCUCAGGCCCCAAGUGGACCUGCUGGAUCAGAAUCUGAAUUCUAGUGAGCUCCUGGGUACACAUUAAAGUUGAAAAGCAGUGCUCUAUCAUAAAGCAGAGUCAACUCUUGAUAACCUGUGGUUUGUAUUGUGGCAAAUUUUUCAUCCCAGGAUAGUUACUUACCCAUUGCCACGUAUCUUGUCAGCCUACACCUAUUGCUGAGUUAGAGGGAACUGCAAACACUGAUAUGCUGCAGCCUCACUGGAGCGGGCUGUCCUUGGGUUUCUAUAUUCACACUACCUUAUAUUAUCUCAGUACUUCCUUAACUUAGAUCCAAAACCAUAGAAACUGAAUUUAUACGAAAUUGUCCUCAGCCAUGUAUAAAGGCAAACUCUUCACAUUUGUUUUUGAUAAAAUAUAGUCACAGUAUAAAUUCAAAAGUCAAGUACAGUAAAGUCCUCACUGAACAUUGUGGAUAGGUUCUUGGAAAUUGUGACUUUAAGAGACACCAUGUACAUCAGGUCCUCAAAUUACACUGUUUUCCUUCAACAUAGUUGCUUUUGUUACAAAGUUAAUAAGAAAAAAAAUUUGUUUCGUUAUGUAUUGUUUCUCUUAAAGUCACAGUUUCCAAGAACCUAUUGAUGAUAAGGACUUACUCUAUAUUGGAUAAUUCACUUUUAUUUGUGGCUCCUCUUAUUCAUUCACCUAAGUACAUUUUAGUAUUUAAGGGGUUUUUUUCUUGAAAAGGUGAAUAUUAUUUUAUUCCUUAUGGAGCAAUUAUCAAACCAUCAAAUUCCAUAUGGUUAGUGAUUGCACAGAGAAAUAGAAUGGCUGGUGAACAUUUUUCUUUAGGUAGAUCAGAAAUAUUCACACUAUUGGCCAGGCAUGGUGGCUCACACCUGUAAUCCCAUCACUUUGGGAGGCUGAGGCAGGGAGAUCACCUGAAGUCAGGAGUUCCAAGACCAGCCUGGCCAAUGUGGCAAAACCCCUUCUCAACUAAAAAUACAAAAAUUAGCUAGGCGUGGUGGCAUGCACCUGUAAUCCCAGUUACUUGGGAGGCUGAGGCAGGAGAAUUGCUUAAACCCAAGAGGUGGAGGUUGCAGUGAGCUGAGAUCCCACCACUGCACUCCAGCCUGGAUGACAAAGUGAGUGAGACCCUGUCAAAAAAAAAAAGAAAGAAAUAUUCAUAUUAUUUUCCUUUGGGAUGUUAGGGGAAGGAGUGGAGAGAAAUAACAUGGGUCCUGUAACCAAGGACACAUGAAACUUUUUUCUCUUCUUUCUUCAUUAAGUCAACAGAUAUUGAGUUCAAACUAUGUGAUAGGUACUGUGCUAGGCAAUAAGGGUGUGCAGAUGGACAAGAUAGUCUGCCACAGGAACUUAUCAAGGUGGCCUCCACAAUAGGUAUGGGUAUAUGGAAACAUAUAUCCAAAUCUCACCAAUCUGAAGUAAUUCUUUACCACAGAUUUGUAUCACCAACAUAACAUGUAUUUGGAUAGUUCAAAGAACUGGAAGAGCUGGGCAUGGUGGCAUGUGCCUGUAGUCCCAGCUACUCAGGACGGCAAGGUAGGAGGUUCGCUUGGGCCCAAGACUUUUGAGUUCAGCCUGGGCAACAUAGCGAGACCCUGUGUCCAAAAUAAAAAAAGAAAAGGAAAAAGAGAACUUGUAGGUUUUCCUACAGGGAUUCAUCGAUCUUCUCUAGUAUGUGAAAAAAUACUACGUUGCCCUAUUUUUAACACCUACAUUUUCCUUCUAAUAACAUUUCAUAGGAAUCUUAUGAAAUAUUUCAGAUACUUAAAUCCUCACUACUUUUUUAUGCCAUAUUGUGCUUUUUUAUUACUAGUUCUUAAUAACUUAUUCUAACAUUUAGAAUAAGUUAUUCCCUCUAGGCAGUAUAUUGUUUUGAUAGAUCACUGAAGGGACAACAGUGAGUCUCUAGAUCUCACUAGUGGAAAUAUUGACACACAAUAUGCACUUUAGGGGUUAUGGAGGAGAUAUAUGACAAUACUGCUAAUCCUGUGGGCUUAGGCUUUGUUCAAGUAUAUUCCGUGGAUUAGAUGAUCAGCAUUUGUUGUAUAACCUUGGAACAUUUCAGAACUCCCCUAAACUUCUGUCUUUUCCAUUUUACUCCAUCAGGUUUAUUGUGACGGCUUAAUGAUUAUGUUAAUAUGUUGUGUGUGUGUGUUUAUGUGUGUGUAUACACACAUGUAUACACACACUGCAUUAUGUGGCAUAGCAAGCGCUCAAAAAACAUUUUCUUAAAAUCUAGUACAAGAGUGGUAAUAUCCAUUAGACUCAAAUAGCUUAGGAGGAUCUGAGUAUAUGACAAAGUCAAAGUUAUACUAUUUCAUUUAAAAUGAGUGAUUUCUGUUAU